AGCGGCUCUCUAGAGCUUGCCUGGGAGCUGCUGAGGAGCUCACGGUAUUCCAGGAAGCUCCCCAUCCAUGCCUCAGCCUGUGGCUCAGAAGCAGGGUCUUCGCAGAAGAUUGCCCCGAGCUGUUGCAAAGCUCACCAUUGUCACCUGCCUGCAACGGCCUCUCUUUUCCACUCUCCAAAUCCCUUGUAUUGGCAGGCUCUAGUCUGGAAUUAUACCGGUGAUGGGAUUCUGGAAAAUCCCUCAGAUUUCUCCAGGAUGCAAGGAGACCAUGGAAGAGGAACAAGCCUGCAAGGGACAGCAGGUGCUAACUGCUAACCGAGACAUAGUGACAAAAAUCCAGCCACAGAGAUAAAGAAUCAGGUUCAUCUGUAGCUACAUCCAGUGGAGAAGUUCUGCUCUUCAACUCCUCUGCUAAGCCACAUGUGUCAGCAGGUGUAGAAUUGAGUGGAACACUUCUUUGGAUUUGCUGUCCGCUGCAGCCUUGGCCCUGGUUUCACAUCCCCUCCCUCACUGACUCGCUGUGUGACCUUGAGCACUGUGUGUCUCUGAGCCUGGUUCAUCCAAGAGUUUACCGACGGCCCUCGUGUGCCAGCCACUGUCCUAGACAGGGACAGACUUUCCCGCCUUUGUGGAGCUUACCCCGGAAGACCUGGCCAGAUAAUGGGCACAAAAAAAGCAGGCUCUUGUCCCCACCCCAGCCUGCCUGAACCCCACCUUGGCCUCCUCUUGCCUCAGCUGCUGCCCAGCCAUCGGCCGAGUGGACAUACCCAGGACGCCCUUGCCCGCCUCCCCCACCACGGCCACAGACCUUUGUCACUCACCAAGGCUGGAAUCCCGUGGCUGAUCCUGCCUCUGCCCUUUGGCUCCCGGGACUCAGCCCACACCACCUGGGUCACAGAGCAUCCCAUUCCCACACACCGUUGUGGCCACCUCACCAGCAGGGGCAGGCCCAUAUGCCCAGGUUUGCCUGGUGAGGAGCUGGGGGCGGGGGUAUGCCCCGCCCCGGGAGCUGACGUCAUAAAAGGAGCUCUGGAGGGCAGCCCACUCUGGCCUGGCCCCACAGCGGCAGUGUCCCUCCCCUCCCCCCACUCCUCUCAGUGGGGGCCCCUCCAGUCCCUGAGAAUUGGUACUACGAAAAGGUGAACUCCUGGGCAGAAUCUUGCCUAGAGCUUGCGGAGUCCAGCCAGGCCCCUGCUGAAGGGCCCCAGACCACCGGCCACUUCUCCCCCGUCCAUCUGACCAGCUGGGCCCCUGCGCCCACCUGGCCUCCACGUUCCCUCUCCUCUCACCCACACCCCUGGCCAUGGCUAACUACUACGAAGUGCUGGGCGUGCAGGCCAGCGCUUCCCCGGAGGACAUCAAGAAAGCCUACCGCAAGCUGGCCCUUCGUUGGCACCCCGACAAGAACCCUGACAAUAAGGAGGAGGCGGAGAAGAAGUUCAAGCUGGUGUCUGAGGCCUAUGAGGUUCUGUCUGACUCCAAGAAACGCUCCCUGUAUGACCGUGCUGGCUGUGACAGCUGGCGGGCUGGUGGCGGGGCCAGCACGCCCUACCACAGCCCCUUCGACACCGGCUACACCUUCCGUAACCCUGAGGACAUCUUCCGGGAGUUUUUUGGUGGCCUGGACCCUUUCUCCUUUGAGUUCUGGGACAGCCCAUUCAAUAGUGACCGUGGUGGCCGGGGCCAUGGCCUGAGGGGGGCCUUCUCGGCAGGCUUUGGAGAAUUUCCGGCCUUCAUGGAGGCCUUCUCAUCCUUCAACAUGCUGGGCUGCAGCGGGGGCAGCCACACCACCUUCUCAUCCACCUCCUUCGGGGGCUCCAGUUCUGGCAGCUCGGGGUUCAAGUCGGUGAUGUCGUCCACCGAGAUGAUCAAUGGCCACAAGGUCACCACCAAGCGCAUCGUGGAGAACGGGCAGGAGCGCGUGGAGGUGGAGGAAGACGGGCAGCUCAAGUCGGUGACUGUGAACGGCAAGGAGCAGCUCAAAUGGAUGGACAGCAAGUAGGCGCUGGCCACCCGGCCCUGCCUUCCCACCACCACCACCGUGCAUGGGGCAGCAAACACGUGGGGCCGCAGACAUAGCCUGAUGGUUAAUAAAUGUGCCAAGUGAGUUCA